GUGUUGAGUUUCUUAUAUACUCUGGACAUUAACCCCUUGUCAGAUGCAUAGUUUGUAAAUAAAGACCAUGUAUGACAGACACACAGCUAACAUACUGAAUGAGGACACGUUGAAAGCUUUUUCUCUAAAAUCUGGAACAAGACAAGGAUAGCCACUUUCACUACUUCUAGUCAACAUAGUACUGGAAGUCCUAGCCACAGUAAUUAUGCAAGAGAAAGAAACAAAGGGCAUCUAAAUUGGAAAGAAAGAAGUCAAACUUCCUGUCUGCAGAUGACAUGAAUUUAUACACACAAAACCCUAAAGAUUCCACCAAAAAACUGCUAGAAGUAAUAAAUUCAGUAAAGUUGCAGGAUACAAAAGCAACAUACAAAAAUCAGUAGCAUUUCUAUAUGCCAAUAGUGAACUAUCUGAAAAAGAAAACAGCAAUCCCAUUCACAAUUGCUACAAAAAACAAAACAAAAACCCUAGGAAGUUUUAACCAAGUAGGCAAAAGAUCUCUACAAUGAAAACUACAAAACAUUGAUGAAAGAAACUGAAGACACAAAUAGUAUCCUAUGUUCAUGGAUUAGAAUAAUUAACAUUAUUAAAAUGUUCAUACUUCCCAAAGUGCUCCACAGAUUCAACACAAUCUCUAUCAAUAUUGCAAUGACAUUCUUCACAGAAAUAGAAAACCCUCAAAUUUAUAGUUUUAGUUCUUACAUUUAGGUCUUUGGUCCAUUUUGAGUUAUUUUUUGUAUAUGGUGUGAGGUAAGGGUCCAACUUCAUUCUUUGCAUGUGGACAUUGUUUUUCCUUGUACCAUUUGUUUAAAAGACUAUAUUACCCCCUCCCUCCCACAUCCCAGUAGAUCAUCUUGGCACUCUUGUUAAAAAUCAGUUGACCGUAAAUGUAAGAGUUUAUUUCUGAACUCUCAAUUCAAUUGAUUAUUUUGAUCUAUAUGGCUAUCUUUAUGUCUUUAUUACUGUCUUCGUUACUUGAUUACUGCAGCUUUGUAGAAAGUUUUGAAAUUGGGAAGUGUGAGUUUUCCAACUGUUCUUCUGUUUCAGGAUUGUUUUGGCUACUCUGGGUCCCUUGCAUUUCCAUAUGAAUUUUAAGAUCAGCUUGUUAAUUUCUGAAAGAAAAAAAAAACAGUUGGGGUUUUCAUAGUGAUUGCUUUCAAUCUGUAGAUCAAUUUGGGGAUGAGCAAUACAUUUGAUUGUAUUAUUGUCAGAAAUAUGUUGACUUUGGAAGUAACAAAUUAGCUAAUUAGAAACAAGUCUUUUGGAGUAAUGAGAAAGGAAUUUGUUGAGCUAGUGCAUCAUUUAAUGGAGGCCUUUGAAACUCAGACUAAGGCAUUCAAAUUUUAUUAGAAAGAUAUUUUUAUAGUUUUUUUCCCUGAAAUUGGUUUGCAUAUGUAGAUGAUUUUAUUAUGAUUCCAGUACUAUUAUAUUUUCCAUACCACUAAAGAGGGCUUUUUCCAUACACAAGUGGAUGUUUUAAAUCAGUCAAAAAGAAUGCCUUUCAAACAGAGUGGCCACUGCUAAGCACUGUAGGAGAAUAAAAGAACUGUAACACACACACACACGGGAGGCUGAGGUGGGAGGGUCACUUGAACCCGGGAGGCAGAGGUUGCAGUGAGCCGAGAUCAUAUCAUGCCACUGAACUCCAGAGCAAGACUGUCUCAAUAAAGAAAAAAAAAAAAAAAAAAAGGCCGGGCAUGGUGGUUCAUGCCUGUAAUCCCAGCACUUUAGGCGGCUGAGACAGGUGGAUCACCUGAGGUUAGGAGUUCAAGACCAGCCUGGCCAACAUGGCCCUGUCUCUACUAAAAAUACAAAAAUUAGCCGGGCGUGGUGAUGGGUGCCUGUAAUCACAUCUACUCCAGUGGCUGAGGCACAAGAAUCACUUGACCACAGGAGGUGGAGGUUGCAGUGAACCCAGAUUGCGCCACGGCACUCCAGCCUGGGCUACAGAGUGAGACUCCAUCUUAAAAAAAAAAAAAAAGAAAAUUGUAACAUACAGCCCUUGCUCUCAGGUACCCUAAAGUUGAAUGGAGAUUAAUUAUGUUUAAGGAGGUGACAUCUGUUAUUUAUCCUUGCUUGCCUAAGACCUUGAAGCAAAGUACUAAGUAGACCAAGAUCAUGAGCGAUUUCUGGAAGAACAGCUCCCUAUUAAAGACUUGGCCUAACCCAGCUUAUUAUGUAGAAAGAGUCUGUCAUUUGCAAGUGGGAUAGCUGUCUCAGUGCAAAUUCACCCAAAACUCUCACUUGGGAAAAAAAAUCCAGAGAGAAAUCCUUACUCAGUAGUGCCACAGUAGUUUUAUUUUGAGAACCUUUAUUACCUGUAACACUGCAACUUUCAAAAAAUAUUUCUCAAUAUUUAUAAUGUUUCUUUAUUCAUAUAAAUAAAAAUUUUAAAAUUUGACUCUGGUAACUAUUUCCUAAGCAAAGGGCUUCCCAGGGAGAGUGGUUAUGCGUGUGUAUAUAUUUUAAUUGUUUUGAAAUGAUCUCGAAUGUAUAGAAAAGUUGCCCAAAUCGUGUAAGGAAGUCCCAUGUCCCCUGCACUCAGAUUCCCAAAUAGUUAACACUUUAUUGCACUUGUUCCAUUGCUCACUGUGUGUGUAUGUGUGCAGGUGUGCAUGCAUGUGCAUAUGUGUGUGUACAUGUGUAUGUAUCCCUUGUUAGUCUUUUUCUGGACCUUUUGAAAGUCAAGAGAGCAAAUUGAAGAGAUGGUGUCUCAUCACUCCUAAACACACUAGUGUUUAUUUUCCCCUAAACAGGGACACUCUCCUACCUAACAACAAACAAACUUCCACAUCAGGAAAUCAAUAUUGGUACAACACUACCAUCCAAUUCAGAUGAGAUUGGGCAUGUUCGGGGUGGUAUGCGAUUCACAGAGCUAAUUCACAUUUUUCCCACCGUCCUAACAAUGUUGUUUUCCUUUCUGGUCCAGAAUGCUAUACAGAGAUACAUAUUGAAUUUAGUUGUCAUAUAACCUCAGUCAGAGACAGUUCCCAGUCUUUCUUGUCCUUGGAUGGUCUACAACCUGAGUUCCUUUCAUGGUAGGAAAACCAAAAAGGAUGCUUUGUGUGUGUGUGUGUGUUUUUUUUUAGUGUGUUUCACCAGGAGGCUCACAAUGUAGACUCCUCCCAACACUGGUGAUGUUAACCAUGAUCACCUGAUCAUGUUGGUUGCGUCCAUUCACUGUUUCCCCCUCUGUAAUCAAGUAGUAUUCCAUGGAAGCAUUCCAAAAUCACGCCAGUAUUCUAUGCCUCAUAGAACAUCUACCCACCAGCCUUAGCGUCCAUUGAAGACUCCUGCCUGAGUCAUCCUCCUCAGUAGUUGUCAAAUGAGAAAUAUUGAAAUCAAAGAGUCGAGAAAGCAAAAUGUAAAGGUGGAAACCUAUGCACUUAAACCCAACUCUUGGCAAGGUAAAGCAUCCGCGGAAACAGCAGGCUCUCGAAGUGAGGAGGCUGCAGCCGGCGCUAGGGCGCAGGCGCAGAAGCUCAGCGUCUCGCUCCCUGCUCCCGGCCCCAGAGGGUUAUCGCGAGUCUUGGAAUAAACUUGCUCGUGCGAUGGCCAAAAAGACCAAAGAAAACAGAGGGACUUUUCCCAGUUGGUGAUAUGGAGCAAGUGCCAUCAGCAGGCAGACUCGUGCAGAUCACCGUGACAGAGGGAUAUGAUUUGAAAGGUUUUAAAGGAGAUACUCCAGUUACCUUUAUUCGAGCAGAAUUCAAUCAAGUGGUUCUGGGAGACUCUGCAAAAAUUACUGUUUCUCCAGAAGGAAGUGCAAAAUACAACUUCACUAGCAGUUUUGAGUUUAAUCCUGAAGGAGGAAUCACUUCAGAUGACCUCGCUCACAAACCUGUGUUCUUAACUGUGACUGAAGUUUUACCAAAGGAAAAGAAACAGAAAGAAGAGAAGACCUUAAUUCUUGGUCAGGCUGUGGUGGACCUUCUUCCCUUACUGGAAGGACAGAGUUCAUUUCAAACAACAGUUCCAUUGCACCCUGUGCAAGGCUCACCCUUAGAAACUCCUAGAUCAAGUGCUAAGCAGUGCAGUCUUGAAGUUAAAGUAUUAGUGGCAGAGCCUUUACUGACCACAGCCCAGAUCUCAGGGGGCAAUCUACUGAAGGUCACGUUGGAGGCUGCUUACUCUGUGCCUGAAUCCUUCAUUCCAACAGGUCCUGGGCAGAACUACAUGGUCGGUCUGCAAGUUCCAUCACUUGGAGAGAAGGACUAUCCCAUUUUAUUUAAGAAUGGAACUCUGAAGCUUGGAGGGGAAAGGGAACCUGUUCCCCGGCCCAAAAAGUGGCCAAUUGCCAACAUUCUGGCUCCAGGAGCUAAUAACAUUCCUGAUGCAUUCAUUGUUGGUGGUCCCUAUGAAGAAGAAGAAGGAGAACUCAACCAUCCUGAGGACAGCGAAUUUAGGAAUCAAGCAGAGUGCAUAAAGAAAAGGAUUAUUUGGGACUUGGAAAGUCGCUGCUACCUUGAUCCUUCUGCAGUGGUCAGUUUUCAGAAGCGAAUUGCCGAUUGCCGGCUUUGGCCUGUAGAGAUCACAAGAGUUCCUCUGGUCACUAUACCCAAAGGGAAAGCUGGCAAAACUGAAAAGACUGAUGAAGAAGCUCAGCUUUCGUUUCAUGGUGUGGCUUAUGUUAAUAUGGUCCCAUUGUUGUAUCCAGGUGUGAAGAGAAUUCGGGGAGCUUUUCAUGUUUACCCUUACCUAGACAGUGUAGUCCAUGAAAAGACCAAAUGUUUAUUGAGCUUGUUCCGGGAUAUUGGCCAUCACUUGAUUCAUAAUAAUAAAAUAGGAGGAAUUAAUUCUCUGCUGUCCAAACAAGCUGUUUCUAAGAAUCUGAAAGAAGAUAAACCAGUGAAAGAAAAGGAUAUAGAUGGAAGGCCUAGGCCUGGGGAUGUGCAGGCACCUAGUAUAAAAUCUCAGAGCUCAGAUACUCCUUUGGAAGGUGAACCCCCUCUAAGUCACAAUCCUGAAGGACAGCAAUAUGUAGAAGCAGGGACAUACAUUGUGUUGGAAAUUCAGCUGGACAAAGCCUUGGUUCCAAAGCGAAUGCCAGAGGAGCUAGCCAGAAGGGUCAAGGAAAUGAUUCCUCCAAGGCCUCCUCUUACCCGUCGGACAGGAGGAGCUCAGAAGGCAGUGAGUGACUACCACAUACAGAUCAAGAAUAUUUCUAGAGCCAUUCUAGAUGAAUACUACAGAAUGUUUGGAAAACAGGUGGCCAAACUGGAGAGUGAUAUGGAUAGUGAAACCUUGGAGGAGCAGAAGUGCCAGCUCAGCUAUGAACUUAAUUGCUCUGGAAAAUACUUUGCUUUCAAAGAACAACUCAAGCAUGCUGUGGUAAAGAUUGUGAGAGAUAAAUACUUGAAGACAACAUCAUUUGAAAGCCAGGAGGAACUUCAGACAUUUAUCAGUGAGCUCUAUGUGUUCUUAGUAGAUCAGAUGCAUGUAGCCCUAAACCAGACCAUGCCAGAUGAUGUCCAAGGCACUGUUGCAACCAUUUAUACAAGCAGUGAACAGCUUCAACUCUUUGCAUUUGAAGCAGAAGUCAAUGAGAACUUUGAGAUGGCAGCAGCAUAUUAUAAAGAGAGAUUGGUCCGUGAGCCCCAGAAUCUGGAUCACUGGUUGGACUAUGGUGCCUUCUGCCUCCUAACUGAAGACAACAUCAAAGCACAAGAGUGUUUUCAGAAAGCCCUUUCCCUCAACCAGAGUCAUAUCCACAGCUUGUUGCUGUGUGGUGUCCUGGCUGUCCUGUUGGAGAACUAUGAGCAAGCAGAAAUUUUCUUUGAGGAUGCUACUUGCUUGGAACCAACUAAUGUUGUAGCCUGGACUUUACUUGGUUUGUACUAUGAAAUUCAAAACAAUGAUAUUCGAAUGGAAAUGGCAUUUCAUGAGGCCUCCAAACAGCUUCAGGCACGGAUGCUUCAGGCACAAGUAACAAAGCAAAAGAGCACUGGUGUAGAAGACACUGAGGAAAGAGGGAAGAGAGAAUCUAGUUUAGGCCCUUGGGGAAUCACAAAUGGUUCUGCAACAGCAAUCAAGGUGGAAGCCCCAGCAGGACCAGGAGCUGCAUUAUCUAUUCUAGACAAAUUUCUUGAAGAAUCCUCCAAACUGCAGUCUGAUUCACAAGAACCCAUUUUGACUACACAAACUUGGGAUCCAAGUAUAAGCCAAAAACCAUCUAACACAUUUAUCAAGGAGAUACCAACAAAGAAAGAAGCAUCAAAAUGUCAAGAUUCAUCAGCUCUUCUGCAUCCCGGCCUUCAUUAUGGUGUUUCUCAAACUACCACCAUCUUCAUGGAGACCAUACAUUUCUUGAUGAAAGUCAAGGCUGUGCAGUAUGUGCACAGAGUGCUUGCACAUGAGCUGUUAUGCCCUCAAGGAGGCCCCAGCUGUGAAUAUUACUUGGUGCUGGCCCAAACACACAUUCUUAAGAAGAACUUUGCCAAGGCAGAGGAAUACCUUCAACAAGCAGCCCAGAUGGACUACCUGAACCCCAAUGUCUGGGGCCUGAAGGGCCAUCUCUAUUUUCUGAGUGGAAAUCAUUCUGAGGCCAAGGCAUGCUAUGAACGAACCAUUAGCUUUGUAGUGGAUGCUUCUGAGAUGCACUUCAUCUUCCUGAGACUGGGGCUCAUCUAUCUGGAAGAGAAAGAGUAUGAAAAGGCAAAGAAAACCUAUAUGCAAGCCUGUAAGAGAUCACCUUCAUGCCUUACCUGGCUAGGACUGGGAAUCGCCUGCUAUCGGCUGGAGGAGCUCACAGAGGCUGAGGAUGCUCUUUCUGAAGCCAAUGCAUUGAACAACUACAAUGCUGAAGUAUGGGCAUAUCUGGCUCUGGUCUGCCUGAAAGUUGGACGGCAAUUAGAAGCUGAGCAGGCCUACAAGUACAUGAUCAAGCUGAAAUUGAAAGAUGAGGCUCUGCUUGCAGAGAUCCACACACUACAGGAAACAGUUGGCUUUGGAAAUCCAUCUUUCUGAUACCCCUCCAGCUGAACAAUUUUCUGCAUGGGACUCUGAGUUCCUUUCCUUCCCAGAGAGUUUUACCGUAUGAAGCCUGGAGCUGGAGAACGAAAGAAUCUUCACUAUAAACAGAGACCCAUUCAUUUAUUUCCAUUGGCUGUGUUACUGGAUGUUUUACUGGUUGACGAGAAACUGGGUCACAAUAAAAAAAUGGAGAUAUGAAACUCAAAA